GUCGAGUAGAAGGACCGCCGCUCCGGCCUCCCGCGACUUCUCGAAGGUGGGCAGGUCCCACCUUGUGGAGGAUGGAGGUGACCGGGGACGCCGGGGUACCAGAAUCUGGCGAGAUCCGGACUCUAAAGCCGUGUCUGCUGCGCCGCAACUACAGCCGCGAACAGCACGGCGUGGCCGCCUCCUGCCUCGAAGACCUGAGGAGCAAGGCCUGUGACAUUCUGGCCAUUGAUAAGUCCCUGACACCAGUCACCCUGGUCCUGGCAGAGGAUGGCACCAUAGUGGAUGAUGACGAUUACUUUCUGUGUCUACCUUCCAAUACUAAGUUUGUGGCAUUGGCUAGUAAUGAGAAAUGGGCAUACAACAAUUCAGAUGGAGGUACAGCUUGGAUUUCCCAAGAGUCCUUUGAUGUAGAUGAAACAGACAGCGGGGCAGGGUUGAAGUGGAAGAAUGUGGCCAGGCAGCUGAAAGAAGAUCUGUCCAGCAUCAUCCUCCUAUCAGAGGAGGACCUCCAGAUGCUUGUUGACGCUCCCUGCUCAGACCUGGCUCAGGAACUACGUCAGAGUUGUGCCACCGUCCAGCGGCUGCAGCACACACUCCAACAGGUGCUUGACCAAAGAGAGGAAGUGCGUCAGUCCAAGCAGCUCCUGCAGCUGUACCUCCAGGCUUUGGAGAAAGAGGGCAGCCUCUUGUCAAAGCAGGAAGAGUCCAAAGCUGCCUUUGGUGAGGAGGUGGAUGCAGUAGACACGGGUAUCAGCAGAGAGACCUCCUCGGACGUUGCGCUGGCGAGCCACAUCCUUACUGCACUGAGGGAGAAGCAGGCUCCAGAGCUGAGCUUAUCUAGUCAGGAUUUGGAGUUGGUUACCAAGGAAGACCCCAAAGCACUGGCUGUUGCCUUGAACUGGGACAUAAAGAAGACGGAGACUGUUCAGGAGGCCUGUGAGCGGGAGCUCGCCCUGCGCCUGCAGCAGACGCAGAGCUUGCAUUCUCUCCGGAGCAUCUCAGCAAGCAAGGCCUCACCACCUGGUGACCUGCAGAAUCCUAAGCGAGCCAGACAGGAUCCCACAUAGCAGCAGCGGGAAGUGUGCCAAGGAAGCUCUGUGGCGUUGUGUUAUUGGUAGACACCCUCAGCCUCAUCAUUUGACUACCUAUGUACUACUCUACCCCCUGCCUUAGAGCACCUUCCAGAGAAGCUAUUCCAGGUCUCAACAUACGCCGUUCCACCAAUUUUUUUUUUAGCCCCACCAGCUUCAGGACUUCUGCCAAUUUUGAAUGAUAUAGCUGCACCAACAAUAUCCCGCCUCCUCUAAUUACAUAUGAUGUUCUCUGUUCAAAAGUAAUUGGCAGUGAUUGGCCAGGCGCAGUGGCUCACGCCUGUAAUCCCAGCACUGGGAGGCCGAGGGGGGCGGAUCGUGAAGUCAGGAGAUCGAGACCAUCCUGGCUAACAUGGUGAAACCCUGUCUCUACUAAAAAUACAAAAAAAAUUAGCCAGCCAUGGUGGCGGGCGCCUGUAAUCCCAGCUACUUGGGAGGCUGAGGCAGGAGAAUGGCAUGAACCUGGGAGGCAGAGCUUGCAGUGAGCUGAGAUUGCGCCACUGCACUCCAGCCUGGGCAACAGAGCGAGACUCCGUCUCAAAAAAAAAAAAAAAAAAAGUAAUUGGCAGUGACUAUGGGCGCACUGCCUAACAUUUAGCCCUGCCCCAUAUGGAACAUGUUAAAAAAAAAAAAAGCCAGGCCGAGCGUGUUGGCUCACGCUUGUAAUCCCAGCACUUUGGGAGGCCGAGGCGGGUGGAUCACGAGGUCAGGAGAUCGAGACCAUCCUGGCUAACACAGUGAAACGUGUUUUUACUAAAAGUACAAAAAACUAGCUGGGCGUGGUGGCAGGAGCCUGUAGUCCCAGCUACUCGGGAGGCUGAGGCAGGAGAAUUGCUUGAACCGGGGAGGCAGAAGUUGCAGUGAGCCGAGAUUAUGCCACUGUACUCCAGCCUGGGUGACAGAGUGACACUCUGUCUCAAAAAAAAAAAAAAAAAGGACAGGCACGACAGUGGCUCACACCUUUGAUCCCAGCACUUUGGAGGCCGAUGCAGGCGGAUCACAUGAGGUCAGGAGUUCAAGACCAACCUGGCCAAUAUGGUGAAACCCCGUCUCUACUAAAAAUACAAAAAUUAGCUGGGCAUGAUGGCGGGUGCCUGUAAUCCCAGCUACUCGGUAGGCAGAGGUUGCAGUGAGCUGAGAGCGCACCACUGCACUCCAGCCUGGGUGACAGAGCUAGACUCCGUAUCUCAAGAAAAAAAAAAAGUUUUGUUUUGUUUUUUUGAGACAGAGUCUCACUCUGUCACCUAGUCUGGAGUGCAGUGGCACAUUCUCGGCUCACUGCAACCCCCACCUCCCAGGUUCAAGCGAUUCUCCUGUUUCAGCCUCCUGAGCAGCUGGGAUUACAGGCACGUGCCACCAUGCCCGGCUAAUUUUUGUAUUUUUAGUAGAGACAGGGUUUUGUCACAUUGGCCAGGCUGGUCUCAAACUCCUGACCUCAGGUGAUCCACCCACCUCAGCCUCCCAAAGUGCUGGGAUUACAGGUGUGAGCCACCACCCCUGGCCAGAAAAAAAAGCUUUUAAAUAAAGUAAUUGUCAGCUUAGGCAACAUAGCAAGACCCUGUCUCUACAAAAAAAAAAUUUAAGUUAGCCAGGCAUGGUGGCACUGACCUAUAAUCCUAGCUACUCUGGAGGCUAAGGCGAGAGUAUCACUUGAGCCCAGGAGCUCAAGGCUGAUCAUGCCACCAUACUCCAGCCUGGAUGAUAGAGUAAGACCCUACUUUUUUUUUUUUUUUUUUAAAAAGGUAACCAUCAAGGGCAAUGAAAAGAAAUGGUCGUAUUUCCAAUUCAUUAUCCUUAUUCUGAAGAUAGUACGGCAGAAUUUUAAGCAGAGAUAGUGGUGAAGAUGGUGACAUUAUAGAGUGUUGACUAUGGCCACAAUCUUGUUUCUCCAGUUAAUGAAUUUUUUUAUGUGUUUGUUUAAAGAUACAUAUUAAGCUUGUAGACCAUAGGGACAUACGGAGAGUCCAUUGCUAAUAUCUCACUCAGUAUUGUGAAAUUCUAUCUCACCACCGUGAAACUCUUCAGUUUUCUAAUUGCUUUAUCAGCAGGGGGUAUAAAAGGUCAUGAAAGCAAUUUCCACAUGCUGUGGCUCCAGGUCUCUGGGUGUGAAGCAGAGCAAGCCUGGUUUGUCCUCCUCCUGUCUCCACACAGACGGCUUCUGCAGGUUUGGUAAUCUACAGUACACUCCUUGCAGGGAAAAGGUGAUGAGUCAUCAUGGACUUAUUUGACCACUUUUUAUGCAUGCUUAGAGGAAAACAGAAUACUGUUAAGAGAUUCAUCUGCUAGUUAUUAAGUAAAGAAAUAUCACAAUAGGCCGGGCGCAGUGGCUCACACCUGUAAUCCCAGCAUUUUGGGAGGCCAAGGUGGGCGGAUCACCUGAGGUCAGGAGUUCGAGACCAGCCUAGCCAACAUGGUGAAACCCCGUCUCUACUGAAAUUAUAAAAAAUUAGCCGGGUGUAGUGGUACACGCCUGUAGUCCCAGUUACUUGGGAGGCUGAGGCAUGAGAAUUGCUUGAACCCAGGAAGUGGAGGUGGAGGUGAGCCGAAAUUGUGCCACUGUACUCCAGCCUGCAACAGAGUGAGACACUGUCACACAAAAAAGAAAGAAAUAUCACAAUAUGUCACAAUAGGCCGGGCGCAGUGGCUCACACCUGCAGUCCCAGCACUUUGGGAGGCCAAGGCAGAUGGAUCACCUGAGGUCAGGAGUUUGAGACCAGCCUGGCCAACGUGACAAAACCCAGUCUACUAAAAAUACAAAAAUUAGCCAGGCGUGAUGGUGGGCACCUGUAAUCCCAGCUACUCAGGAGGCUGAGACAUGAGAAUCGCUUGAACCCAGGAGGUGGAGAUUGCACUGAGCUGAGAUCCUGCCACUGGGCUCCAGCCUGGGUGACAGAAUGAGACUCUGUCUUUAAAAAAAAAAAAAAAAGAAAAUCACAAUAAGUCCUAGGGUAAAGAUGGGGGUACAGAAAACAAUUAAAUAGAACAAAAACAACUGUUUCCUUUUCCUGUGAUUCAAGAAGGGCUUAGAUCUUCUACUCAGCAUCCUUUUACUAAUGCCCUCCAUUGGCUCUCACCCCAACAUUUCCUUUUUUAUAGCUUAUUUUGUAAUGCCUCCUUAAUUAUCCUUUAAUAGAAGCCACCGCUGAUAAGCUACCUACACUCAUACAGAAGCAUUAAUAUAAUGCCCCAGAUGUACUGUUUCAGGGCAAAAAGGAAAAUAAUUUCCAACAAAGUGGUGUGUGUUUCACUGUCAGAUGCUUGCACUUACACACGGAAUCGCUGUGCAUCCGACAGAGGCUGAUUGGCACAUGGGGCACGGGGAUUGUCAGCUCAAACACCGUCAGCAGCGUUGCCCUUGGAAAUGGGAUUUCCCAGAACAGUAAACGUGUCUGUCCUUGAUUUACAGAGUAGCUACAUUCCUAGGAAAUCCAGGGUACAUUAAAACUCACCAUGUUACCCAGGCUGGUCUCAAACUCCAGGCCUCAAGCAAUCCUCCCACAUCAGCUUCCCAGAAUUUUGGGAUUACAGGCAUGAGCCACCACACCCAGCCAGAAUAUUUUAUUUCUGUUAGACACACAGAGCGUUCGUUGACUCGUCUGGGCGUUAGUGUUAAUAUUCUGUACUUGAAGCAAGCCCACCAAGCGGCUGAACUGGGUGGAUAAUGGAAAAUGUCCUGUGGAUUUGGGAGUGAGACAAACCGGCUUGAGUCUAACCUCUCAGUUAGUCUAAGGCUCCAAGCUUGAAAGGGUUAAAUGAAGUACUAUAUUUGUUUUGUUUCGUUUUCGUUUUGUUUGAGGCUUUGCUCUGUUGCCCAGGCUGGAGUGUAGUGGCACAAUCUCUGCUCACUGCAACCUCCAUCUCCCAGGUUCAGGCGAUUCUCUUGCCUCAGCCUCCAGAGUAGCUGGGAUUACAGGUGCCCGCCACCACACCCGGCUAAGUUUUUUUUGGUAUUUUUAGUAGACACAGGGUUUCACCAUGUUGGCUAGACUGGUCUCAAACUCCUGACCUCAAGUGAUCCACCUGCCUUGGCCUCCCAAAGUGCUGGGAGUAUAGGUGGUGAGCCACCACGCCUGGCCUAAAUGAAGUACCACAUGACCGACAGACCGACCUGGGGAACAUAGCAAGACCCCAUCUCUACAAAAAUGUAAAAAAUAAAAAUUAGCCGGGUGUAGUGGUACAUGCCUGUAAUCCUAGAUACUCGGGAGGCUAAGGCAGAAGGAUCACUUGAGCCCAGGAGUUCGAGGCUACAAUGAGCUGUGAUCGUGCCACUGCACUCCAUCCUGGGUGGCAGAGUGAGGCCCUGUCUCAAAAUAAAUAAUCCAGUCCCCCCCAAGAAAGGAAUGAAGUGCUAUAAUGAGAAAAAUCCUAGUACCUAACAUAUAGUAGACAGUGGAGAGUGGUUCUCUUUCGUUUCUCAGGGGCAGACAGAUGGGGUGCUGGAGUCCUCUAUCAAAGAGUCAGAGCUCUAUCCCAGAUGUGUAAUGAACGUGGUCACAGACAUAUUGUCCCAUUACCAUUUACCUUCCCUAUAACCACUGUGCCUCCAGCCUUGUAGAAUAGACACAUAGGAGCGCAGCAAUACGUCUAAAAAUAGGAGUGAGAGAGGGCAGGGCAUGCCCGUUCUUGUGGUAGAAGAAAAGAAUGUCAAAGAAAGCAGCUGGGACUAAUGAACUUUACAUUAGCCAUAUUCCAUUAUUUCAGCUUAAGUCAAAUGUCGGUCCUCAUGAGGCAACUGGCUUUGACAGGAGCUACGCUAAUUACCACUUACCAACCUUUAAUUUCUGGGUAAAAGCAAAAGAGAAAAACUAAUGGAUUUUUCAUUUUCCAGAGAGACAAGAAUAAAAUAAUAGUAGUCUGUAGAAAAAAGAAAACCUGCAUCAAUUACAAGAAUUAUUAAUGUAUCUUUAAUAAAUAACCACAUUAUUUAGCUGUUUAAUUUCCUAA